ACAGAGCUACCCUAGUGUCCCCAGGCUGAGGAGGUAGUGACUGGCAUACAUGGCUCAGUUUGUCCAGGUCCUGGCUGAAAUAGGUGACUUUGGUCGCUUCCAGAUACAGCUAUUGAUCCUGCUGUGUGUUCUCAACUUCCUGUCUCCCUUCUACUUUUUUGCCCAUGUCUUCAUGGUCCUAGAUGAGCCCCACCACUGUGCAGUGGCUUGGGUGAAGAACCACACUUUCAACCUGAGUGCUGCUGAACAGCUGGUACUGAGCGUGCCCCUGGACACUGCAGGUCACCCAGAGCCCUGCCUCAUGUUCCGGCCACCCCCCGCCAAUGCCAGCCUGCAGGACAUCCUCAGCCACCGCUUCAAUGAGACGCAGCCUUGUGAUAUGGGCUGGGAAUAUCCUGAGAACAGGCUCCCAUCCCUGAAGAAUGAGUUCAACCUGGUUUGUGAUCGGAAGCACCUGAAGGACACCACACAGUCAGUGUUCAUGGCUGGGCUCCUUGUUGGCACCCUCAUGUUUGGGCCCCUCUGCGACCGGAUUGGCCGCAAGGCCACAAUCCUGGCGCAGCUGCUCCUCUUCACCCUCAUCGGCCUGGCCACAGCUUUUGUGCCCAGCUUUGAGCUCUACAUGGCCCUGCGCUUUGCUGUGGCUACUGCCGUCGCUGGACUUAGCUUCAGCAAUGUCACCCUACUGACAGAAUGGGUGGGGCCCUCAUGGAGGACGCAGGCCGUGGUCCUGGCCCAGUGCAACUUCUCCCUCGGGCAGAUGGUGCUUGCGGGACUCGCCUACGGUUUCCGCAACUGGAGGCUCCUUCAGAUCACCGGCACUGCGCCUGGCUUACUGCUCUUCUUCUACUUCUGGGCUCUGCCAGAAUCUGCACGUUGGCUCCUGACCCGUGGGAGGAUGGACGAGGCGAUACAACUGAUCCAGAAGGCGGCCUCGGUCAAUAGGCGGAAACUCUCCCCGGAGCUCAUGAACCAGCUGGUCCCAGAGAAGACAGGCCCCUCAGGGAAUGCCCUGGAUCUGUUCAGACACCCCCAGCUCCGGAAGGUGACCCUGAUUAUCUUCUGUGUCUGGUUUGUGGACAGUCUGGGGUACUACGGCCUGAGCCUCCAAGUGGGGGACUUCGGCCUGGACGUCUAUCUGACGCAGCUCAUCUUUGGAGCUGUUGAGGUGCCUGCCCGCUGUUCCAGCAUCUUCAUGAUGCAGAGGUUUGGCCGCAAGUGGAGCCAGUUGGGGACCUUGGUCUUGGGUGGCCUGAUGUGUAUCAUCAUCAUCUUCAUCCCAGCAGAUCUGCCCGUGGUGGUCACCAUGCUGGCUGUGGUGGGGAAGAUGGCCACAGCUGCUGCCUUUACCAUCUCCUAUGUGUACUCUGCCGAGCUUUUCCCCACCAUCCUCCGGCAGACAGGCAUGGGGCUGGUGGGCAUCUUCUCACGGAUCGGGGGCAUCCUCACACCACUUGUGAUCCUGCUGGGAGAGUACCACGCUGCCCUCCCCAUGCUCAUCUACGGCAGCCUCCCCAUCGUGGCCGGCCUGCUGUGCACCCUGCUGCCAGAGACGCAUGGCCAGGGCCUGAAAGACACCCUCCAGGACCUGGAGCUGGGGCCUCACCCACGGUCCCCCAAAUCAGUGCCCUCAGAGAAGGAAACAGAGGCCAAGGGAAGAACUUCCAGCCCGGGAGUGGCCUUUGUGAGCAGCACAUACUUCUGAUUGAGGUCUCUAAGAGCUGGACCAUCAGCAGCAGGGAGCUGCCUAAACACCUCCUUGGAUAUGGCCAGGACCCACAGGGACACAGGGCAAGACCAGCCUUGCUUAUGGAGGCAGGACACCACAAUCUGGCCCAUGGCUGUCACCUCCUGCCGAGUCCAAUCCCAGACUGGGAACCACCAUCUGAGACAGGACCUCCCGGCCUCCUUCACCUUUCUCAUCUCCAGAGCCCUGCCCCCAAUACUCUGUCUGGGUUAGGAUCUUGGGUAUGUCUUGGAAUUAACUUGUCCUCUAACAAUCUUCAUGGGGUAUGGCUCUCUUGAUCUCCUCAAUCUGGAGUCCCCUGCCCUCAAAACACAGUGAUGUUCAGAACAGAACACAAGGUAAGCCCUUUCCAAUUUGUGGGAACAGGAGGGGAGAGGAAACAAAUGUGAAGUUGUGGACUCUACCCAGGCAGGUGGAUGAAAAUGCUGUGGAUAAAAGGAAGGUUAUGAUUCCUUCUAGCGGAUGGACCAGAUUCCUCUGGCUAACGUAUGGCCCCAUAGGUCACUGGGUCAUACAGAGAGAAGAUUCAGUUCAGCCUAAAUCAAAACUUCCACCUUGUGUUCACUUCAAAGAUGGCCCAACCCCCGCCCUACACUCAGCUCAUGCCUAACCUAUGUGUGGCUCAGGGACCAGCUUGGGGAAGGAAAGGAGGUUUGUUCUGCUCCCCGCCUCACCCCGCCUCCUCCUGCUCAUGCUCAGCUGCUUCUGGACCUUCCAGGGCCCAUGCAGGGUGAGGGAAAGGGUAGAGGUCUUUUCACCGAGCUGCUGCUGGUUGCAGUUCUUUCUGGUGCACAUUGGCUAAUGCCAGUUGGUGUGUUUUGUCAGGCUUCUGAAAGCUGCCUUUUCCACGGGCCAUCUUCUUGGGCUUCUCAGAGAUCUUCUCAGGCCUUGGUAUUGUUCCUUAGAAUGAGCAAUAUGCUCCCAAUGCACUCCCAGCUCCUCUUGGGACCCUUCUCCAGCCCCACCCAGCAUUGCUCCUACAACCUGUCCUACAGCUGGCAGCCCCUGACCCAACCAAGAUGGCCUUCUUGGCUGGGCGUGGUGGUUCAUGCCUGUAAUCCCAGCACUUUGGGAGGCUGAGGCGGGCGGAUUACCUGAGGUCAGGAAUUUGAGACCAGCCUGGCUGGCAUGGCAAAACCCUGUCUCUACUAAAAAUACAAAAAUUAGCCCUAUAUGGUGGUGCAUGCCUGUAAUCCCAGCUACUUGGGAGGCUGAGGCAGGAGAAUCGCUUGAACCUGGGAGGCGGAGUU